AGUGUUGCCCUUCUCGUCUAGAUGGCGGCCAUUCCAGCUUUCCUAAGCGUCCAUUAUCUACCAGGUUCCUCCCGCACCCACGUUCACCCGCAAGAGCAGCCGGGAGCGCUGUGGACUCCCUAGCCCGAAGUCUCCUCUUGGCUGUACGCACGGACCGCAAAAGAAGGGACAUGAAAGUGCUUUGCAACCAAAGGAUUCCUAUGAGGCCGGGCCUGCAAUGAUGUGAAGCCCCUGAGGACGCCCGAAUGGUGGCCCAAAGUCUCUCUGACGCUCACCAUGCCCUGACUAUCAUGCUAUCUGAACGACUUUGGCUGGGACUGGAGCUCUUAAAUUUUACAAGAAGGAAAAUCAGUUCUGACCCACCACCAUACAACUUCCUUGAGGCGCGAGGGUGUCCACAAUCUCCACAGAGGCGGCAUUGGGUCACCGCUGGAGGAUGCAGCAGGAGGGAGGACCCGUGAGGAGCGCCCCCUGUAGGACCGGAACCCUGGAGGGUUCGCGGCAAGGGUCUCCGGGGCAUAGGAAACGGGCAUCCCCCAAGGGUAGUCUGAGUUCCGCCCAGCCCCAUUCCUGGAUGCUCACGCCGUCUCCCCUAAACUCCCACUGCGCUCACCGGGAGCCCAUCUCAUCAUCACCACAGCCCGUGGCUAAUGGGCCAAAACAGAAGAAGAAAAGCAACUGGCGGAGUACAACGCGCCUGCGCAUUAUCAGACUCAGGGACAGGCUGGAACCUCGCCCCCUAGCUAUCCUAGAAGACUAUGCGGACCCGUUUGAUGUUCAGGAGACUGGCGAAGGCUCAGCAGGAGCUUCAGGAGCCCCAGAGAAGGUCCCUGAAAAUGAUGGCUACAUGGAGCCCUAUGAGGCUCAAAAGAUGAUGGCCGAGAUCCGGGGCUCCAAGGAGACAGCAACUCAGCCCUUGCCUCUGUAUGACACACCCUAUGAGCCAGAGGAGGAUGGGGCCACCGCGGAAGGUGAGGGGGCCCCCUGGCCCCGGGAGUCCCGCCUGCCAGAGGAUGAUGAGAGGCCCCCUGAGGAGUAUGACCAGCCCUGGGAGUGGAAGAAGGAGCGGAUUUCCAAAGCCUUUGCAGUUGACAUUAAGGUCAUCAAAGACCUACCUUGGCCUCCACCUGUGGGACAGCUGGACAGCAGCCCCUCCCUGCCUGAUGGGGACAGGGACAUCUCCGGUCCAGCCUCGCCCCUCCCUGAGCCCAGCCUGGAGGACAGCAGCGCCCAGUUUGAAGGACCGGAGAAGAGCUGCCUGUCACCUGGCCGGGAGGAGAAGGGGCGGCUACCUCCCCGACUCUCUGCAGGGAACCCCAAGUCAGCCAAACCCCUAAGCAUGGAGCCCAGCAGCCCCCUGGGGGAGUGGACAGAUCCAGCACUGCCUCUGGAAAACCAGGUCUGGUAUCACGGGGCCAUCAGCCGAACCGACGCCGAGAACCUGCUCCGGCUGUGCAAAGAGGCCAGCUACCUGGUGCGCAACAGUGAGACCAGCAAGAAUGACUUCUCCCUCUCCCUCAAGAGCAGCCAGGGAUUCAUGCACAUGAAGCUGUCCCGAACCAAGGAACACAAAUAUGUGCUGGGCCAGAACAGCCCGCCCUUCAGCAGCGUCCCUGAAAUUGUGCACCACUAUGCCAGCCGCAAGCUACCCAUUAAGGGAGCCGAACACAUGUCCCUGCUCUACCCUGUGGCCAUCCGGACUCUUUAGAUGUGAAGCCAGGGCACUGUGAUAGACCUGUACCCAGCCCUGUGCCCAUCACCUGGCUGAGGGCUGUGGCUCUUGCCAGGGACGUGAUCUUUCAAACCUUUCUUCUCCUGGGAUCCAGUAGAAGCUGGAGAUUCCUUAAUUUAUUCUAAAGGGAAAGGGCUCCUGGGGCCUUGGAGUAAGGGGUUGUCUGGAGCUGGGGAAAGAGGAAUCCCUGGAGAGAAAGGAUAGCCCCUGGAGGAAGGGGGUUCCAGAGCUACUGGGAUGGUAGGGAGUUUCAGACUGGCAGCUCCGGCUCCUUUCCGACCUUAGGGCAGAGGUGGUGACCUCCACCACCACCACCCUCUCCCCACUGGGUCCGUGCGAGGUAGUGCAGAAUUCGGCCCCUUGGGGCGCCUUACCACCUCUCUGCCUCCGUCCCCGACUUCCACCCCAGACCGUCGGAGGGCUCCGCCCAGAGUCUGGUAAGAGGUUUGGGGAAGACAGGCCCCUGGGAAGCAGCCGGCUUUGGGGGGUGGGGAGAGAAGGGGAGGGGCUCGGGCAGAGGGAACUGUGCAGUCCCCAGGCCGCCCCGGCUCCGGGCCAGAGGCAAUAAAUAAACCCGAUCCUGCCGGGCACAGCCGCGCCCGCGCCUCCGGCGCCGUCCCCGGGCUGACGGGGGAGGGAGCGGAGAAGCGAGCGCAGAUUCUGCGUAUAAAUCAGCUCUGGAGCAGACACAGCCCGGCUGUGAAAAGCA